CAAAAAUAAAUAAAUGAGUAUAAGUAAAUGGCUAAACUGCAAAUGCAGUUUAAAAUUUUUUCCUUUAUUGUUGUCAUUUUUAACAAACCUCAAAACCAAGAAACUGAGAUCUUUAUCUUGUAUCAAGAAUGACAUUCAUCUUCAGAAGAUACAGAUUUCACUAAAUCAGUGUCAAAUUAGAUCUAGUGAUAAUUAAAAACCCAGUAAUGUUUUUGUGUCAUCCUUGCAGGAAUCAAGACUGGUCACACUUGGACCAGUCAUUUAUUCAUUCACUCAAAAAAUAUUUGCUCAGUGUUGAUUGUGUGCCUGUUGUUUUCUAGGCACCAAGUCAAGAUGCCAUAGUAACAAAGCAAAGCCCCUUCCCACGUGGAACUUUCAUUCCAAUGGGGAGAGAGAAAAACAAAACAGCUGGUGGUGAGGGGCCUGGGAAGGGGCAGGGCCUGUGUGGUGGGGGUGGAUUGCUGUUUGCUGUAAAGUGAUGGGGAGGCCCUGGAUGGUGAUGAUAUUGGAGUCAAAAUCUGAAGAAAAGAUGUGGUAUGGUGUAUUCCUGUGGGCACUGGUGUCUUCUCUCUUCUUUCAUGUCCCUGCUGGAUUACUGGCCCUCUUCACCCUCAGACAUCACAAAUAUGGUAGGUUCAUGUCUGUAAGCAUCCUGUUGAUGGGCAUCGUGGGACCAAUUACUGCUGGAAUCUUGACAAGUGCAGCUAUUGCUGGAGUUUACCGAGCAGCAGGGAAGGAAAUGAUACCAUUUGAAGCCCUCACACUGGGCACUGGACAGACAUUUUGCGUCUUGGUGGUCUCCUUUUUACGGAUUUUAGCUACUCUAUAGCAUACAUCCUUAUGCUGAGAUGUUGAACUUAAACUUUAUGGAAUCCUCCAAAAGAAUACAUUAUGGAGUGUAGUGUUUUCUUAGUUCUUCAAAGGGAAGCAACUUGGAUGAACAGGAACAUGAAGGACAACACAUCUCAGCCUUUUCUUCAUUUUGAAGCUCCUAGAAUUGAAGACUUAUGUGGACUCCUAUUGUUCUCAACCAAAACAAGUCUUUUGGCUUUCUUUUUUGUAGAUAUUUGAUUUAAGCAGUUUUCAUGUGUACCUUUACCCAAGCCAAGUCAACAGUGUCUCUGGGGUGGCAUCCUUUGCACUGAAAUUUACAGUAUUCUGUGAGAUGUCGCAUAUUUUGAAGAAACCGUGGAAGAUACUGGUUUAUUUCAAAUGAGCAGAGUAUGUUGUAUUAAAAUCUUAUCUAAUCUUGAUUAAAAUUUGGCAAACUCUUUUCUUUGCUACAUCUUAGUGACAAUAAAUGCCAAAUAGGUUUUGGUUGAGUAUAGUUUUGAAAACAAAUUUGGUGAAAUAAAGCAGGAAAAAAAAUUUAAGUAUAACUCAAGUAGUGGCUUUGGUUCCACUGUUUAUAAAUAAAAAGUAGAUAACAAUGAAUAAUGUGACAUUUUCUGGACAACUGUCUUGACUUCUGAUUAAGAUAUUUUAAGAGAUGUGAAUUUGUUAUUUUGUAUGUUUUAUCAAAAUAAGCUAGCUAAUUUAGACUUUUUAGAUUUUCUGUACCACCUUUCCCUAUCACUUUUAAUUCUCUUAAUUUUAUUUCAUUUAAUUGGAAACAUACAUACCCUAUUAAAUGGCUUGAGUUGGAAAUUUUAAGCCAGAUUUGUUUGGACAUUGAGGCACACAUAAGAUACUUUAGGCAUUCUGUCAUAGUUUUUCUUAGUGACUUUGGUAUACUAAUGACCCUUGAGAAACUAUAGAAGUGCAUCUGAAACUAGAGUUAGUGGUUAUUGAUUUUUUAGCUUAAUGUGUUUACCUAGUGGUAACUCUUCAGCCCACUUUUACAGUAUUGGGUAUCAACUCCCAGAAAGUGCCUAAAGUUUAAUGUUCAGAUAUGUACCCACUCUCCCCUUUACAUUUUUAUUCAAAAGAAUUUAUAUCUUUAAAGAGAUUUAAAUAUCAAGAGUUUUUUUAAAACUUAAUUUUAGCUAUUUAAAUUUUUAUUCUACUGCCUAACUUUCUUUUUCAUUAAAAGGCCUGAAAACUGUGACUCUUUGAGAGGGAAAGAAUCGCAGAAAUUAAGUAUUUAAUGUGAUCCUUUCCACCUAAACUGUUUUGUAUGGAAUACAAUCAGUGUGGUGGUAGUGGUGGUGGUUAUCUGCAAAAUAGUUUCUGGUGAUUAAAUCUGACUUUUUUUUUUUUUUUUCUUUUAAAUGAGACGGAGCCUCACUGUGUUGCCCAGGCUGGAGUGCAGUGGUGCAAUCUCAGCUCACUCCAACCUCUGCCACCCGGGUUCAAGCGAUUCUCCUGCCUCAGUUUCCUGAGUAGCUGGGAUUACAGGCACCUGCCACCGUGCCCGGCUAAUUUUUGUAUUUUUAGUAGAGAUAGGUUUCACCAUCUUGCCCAGGCUGGUCUUGAACUCCUGACCUUGUGAUCCACCCGCCUCGGCCUCCCAAAGUGCUGGGAUUACAGGCGUGAGCCACCGCGCCUGGCCAUAAAUCUGACAUCUUUAAAGGAAAGUUUUCAUUGUGAGAUUAAGGCUUAACAGCCCAUGAGGUCAUAUACACAUGAACGUAUCUAUUCCAUUUAAAGCAAUACACACUCUGGCUUCUGAUUAAAAAUAGCCAGGAGGAGAGUCUCUGAAUCUACUGUGAUUCUGGAGUCUGCCCAAUUUGGAAAAAAAAAAAAAAGAAAAAAGUCAGGAGGACCAAUUUGCCAGGGAAACUCAUAGAAAAGAAUUACAAAGAGAUCACAAAAACUGGACAUAUUCUUUUGACUAAUUAGACCACUUAUGGCUGGGCGCAGUGGCUCACACCUAUAAUCCCAGCACUUUGGGAGGUCGAUGUGGGAGGAUUGCUUGAGCCCAAGAGUUCAAGACUGGCCUGGGCAACAUAGUGAGACCUUGUCUCUACUACAAAAUAAAAAAAAAUUAGCUGGGCGUGGCCUCAGCUACCCAAGAGGCUAAAGUGGGAGGAUCACUUGUGCCUGGGAGGUUCAGGCUGCUGUGAGCCGAGACCACGCCACUGAACUCCAGCUUAGGCCACAGGGCAAGACCCUGUCUUAAAAUAAUAUUACUAAUUUUGGUAAUUAACUUAUCAAAACUAUAGUGACAUAUACACGGGCAGAAACUUAUAAGUAGAGUUGUAAUGCAGCCAAAUAUUCUUACAAAUUCCCUAACAAGAAGCUCAAAUCUUUCUCACAGGCAAAUUGUAAAAAUUCUAGUUUUUUGUUUAAAGAGCUGUGAUUUUCAAAAGUAUCCCUUCAGUUUAAGAAAUCUGGGGAAUUGGUAACUUUUCUUAUGGGAAAUGAUUGCCAUCAUCUCUACUGAAGGAUGCCUCUUACUGAAAAAUGUCUUUUGAAGGAGUUCUUGCCUAAAGCAUUCUUUGGAUGUAAUUUCAUACACUAAACAUAUAGACCAGUAGUUAGUGGGCCCCUCCUCUUAAACAGUAACUUUUGAAGUACUGAUACAUGAUUAAAAUGUUAGAUAUUUUUCACUGGAGCUAAGACUUAAAAUUAGGGCAUUUUGAAAGGUGUAUUUGUUUCUGUUUCUUGUUUGAUAUAUUUUGGUUAUCUACUCUUUUAAAAAACUAAACGUAUAAAAGGUAUCUUCAAAUUACUGAGUGUUUCAUCCAUCCCAGUAGGUGAAGUAUUCUCCAGUGAAUAAAUCUAUAUAUAUAUAUAGAUUUUAAAUAGCUUGAGCGGUGUAGCUUGAAAUGUUUUCAGGGAAAGACUAUUUGAAUCAUAAGGAAUAGCUUUGAUUUUCUUUUUUAUGUCUCAAAUAUAGAAUUAUUUGGGGGUGGUCACUCAGAUGGAAGAAUAUUGGCAAUUGUGUUGAACAUUUUACCUUAUAUAGUUUUGAGAAUUUUUGCCAAAAACUGAUUUCUUAGAAAUAUCCUCCCCCAGCUGUGCUUUGGUUUUUUGGUUUUUUUGUUUUGAGACGGAGUCUUGCUCUGUCGCCCAGGCUGGAGUGCAGUGGCAUGAUCUCGGCUCACUGCAAGCUCUGCCUCCCGGGUUCACGCCAUUCUCCUGCCUCAGCCUCCCGAGUAGCUGGGACUACGGACGUCCACCACCAUGCCCAGCUAAUUUUUUGUAUUUUUAGUAGAGACGGGGUUUCACCGUGUUAGCCAGGAUGGUCUCAAUCUCCUGACCCGCCUCCACCUCCCAAAGUGCUGGGAUUACAGGCAUGAGCCACCACACCCGGCCUCUGCUUUGUUUUUUAAAAAAAAAGAAAUGCAAGAGAGGGAGGGAGGCAGCCUCCUGACCAUAAAAGCUGAUUUCUUGAUUUUUUUUUCUUUUUUUUUUGAAAUGGAGUCUUGCUCUGUCUCCAAGGCUGGAGUGCAGUGGCAUGGUCUCAGCUCACUGCAGCCUCCGUUUCCUGGGUUCAAGUGAUUGUCCUGCCUUGGCCGCUGAGUAGCUAGGAUUACUGGCACCCGCCACAAGGCCCAGCUAAUUUUUGUAUUUUUAGUAGAGACAGGGUUUGAUUAUGUUGGACAGGCUGGUCUCAAACUCCUGACUUCAAGUGAUCCACCCGCCUCGGCCUCCCAACGUGAUGGGACUAUAGACAUGAGCCAUCAUGCUUGGCCUUCUUGAUUCUUGAAUACGGGGUUUUGAGGUGAAAGCAUUUCAUGAAAACUUAAGUUCAUACACAAGAGCAUCAUGAAUAUUCUAAAAGAGGUAUCUGUGCUUUUUUUGUGACCACAAAAUAUUACUUCUUAUGAAAUGUUUACACUAGGUGAGGAAAAGUUCAUUAAUUACCUUUAAACCGUUCCUUAUUUUUUUUAAGAUUUUAAAUUGUAUUUUGGCUUUUGCCUCCAGUAUCCUUUCUGGUUGCUCUGGUUUGAAUUAAGUUCCUAUUAUGCUGCAGCACAUAUCAACCUUCCCUAAGUAACCAUUUCCUGGAAUGUGAAGCAUCGGUGCCAUUAGCAGACCAUAUGCAGAAAUGUCGUGUACUUGCAUUUCUUUUUUGUGCACUCUAUAAGGCUGGUUGUGACUCAGAUCAGCUUAACUUUUUAUAUUAUGUUAUUUCACUAACUGCUACAGUCAAAAUGAUCAAAUCUUUGUACAAUAGAAAAUUAUUUAAAUUUUAUUUUUCUACUGACAUUUCUAAUUCUAGUGUAAAUGUUUAUCAAUAAAAAAUUACUUUCAAUUCUGAGUUGGAAUUAUAUUUCUUUUUGGUGGCUAAUGAGUUUAAUCUUUUGUAAUAAAAUUGACUUCAGUUUUCAUUUUUUAAAUAACUUAAUAUCUAGCAUGUGUAACUUUUUUUAUGUUCUACUUCUUACUAAUUUAUGAUAAAAUUCUUGUUCAAAGUUGUGAUUAAACCGUACUUAACAUGUGAA